UCCCCCAGGGAUAAGGUUCUUGCCAUCCUUGGUAUUGGUAUGGCUGCUUUUCUGGAUUUGAGGUGUCCACGCCUCUGCAUGUGUCCCCACCGUAAGGCUGAGGACCCCUCUCGGAUGCAGGUGCCCCCGGCUCAUGCUUCCAAAACCCCCUCUUGAUUUGUCACUGUAUGGGGUAAGGCAUAGUUUCCUGGCUGUGUGGAUGUAAGAUACCUGAGUCUCAAGCGGGAGACUCCACUGUAGACCCUGUCCCUGGGACCAGAGACUUCUCUGGUGUAGACUUUCCAAGGUGGGAGAUUCCAGCCCCCCACCCUUGGCAUGGGGCAUCUCAGUGGAGAUGACUACCUCUACCCCAGGCCCUAACGCAUCCUUCUUCUGGAGUCUCAGAGCCUCUGUGUGGCCACGUCAGCAGCCACCUGGGUUAAGGAUCACCCUUCAACAUCACUUCUCAGAGCUCCUUGCUGCAGAGGCGGAAGCUCUCCCAGAUCAAAGGUGCCUCAUGACAAAGACCACUCUGUGGGCACAUGACGGCCCCCAAGGUUAAGGACCACCCGGUGUUAGUUUCCCAGGGCUGACCUCCUGCCCCUCCCUCCUCGAGUCUUUGUGUGGUGGUAUCAUCUUCCCUGAGAUGAAGUCUGGGGGGCUCUUCUUUACUGGUUUUGGCUCUGAUUUUAGCGUGUUGGCUCCUGUGAGGCUGGUGUCCUGCUCACCUCCCCCCGCCCCGCCACCCGCCUUGUGGGUCCCUUCCCUGUGGGGAUGUGUGUUCCUCUUGGGUAAGUCUCCUCCUGGGCCGAGGUUCCCAGAUUCCUCAGUGCUCUUGGAGAGCCUUUGCUGCUGGAGCACAGGUUCUUCACGCCUGAGAGUGGACCUGCGAUCACCACCUUCCUUGGAGGAUCUUGGUGGAUGCCCCCCUGACUACAGCAAAUGGGGCUCUUUCUUCUCUGGCGGCGUCUCUGCUUCGAGACUCAGGCUCCAGCUUCCCUUCUCUCUGGUCCUUUGCUGGGGGGACCAGAGGUACAGAUACCCUCAUGAUAUAAGGAUUUUCUUAGCGGGGAAGGUGUUGUCUCUACUGUGGCUAAGGCUCCAGCCUCUCUAGGGGACAAGUACCCUGGGCCUCUGGCACUUGCCCCUUCUCUGUGGAGGAGCUGCCUCCUCACUGGGUCUCAGCUGUAGCCGACUUCGAUGUCACACUGUUCUGUCUGAAACAUCACCUCCCUGGGUUAGCGCUCUUGUUCCCCUCCUUCUGGCUUGUGACCCCUCCAGGACUUCCUUCUCUUGCUGCCACAGUGUGGUCUCCUCUCUGUGGGUAUUCUUCCUCUGCACUAGGAUACCAGUCCUUUCCGUGUGGAGACACAGGGAGGGCGUCACCUGCCUAAGGUGUUGAUUGCCUUGUUUAGGGGUGUAGACCAUGAGACCUCUUCUCUCUCUGGGCUGGAGCACCUGCCCAUGACCCUCUGUUGGGUUCUUGGGAUGGAAAGAGGGAGUGUAAACUCUCGUUUCACAUUCUUGUUCCCCCUAUGCAGUAAGAGGCUUUUCUGUGUUGGGGUGUUGGACUUUGGUGAGGAUCCCUGCACACCUGAGCUCUGGUGUCCAGGCCCUUGCCUUGUGUGAGCUCCCUGGGUCAAAGGGGCUUUCCCCUCCUCAGCCUGAAUCCCCACUGUGGCACCUUCUCCUGGGUCCUUUUGUUGGUUGCUUUGCCUUCUUAGAGAUUCCCCAGGUAGGGCGUGAUAGCUGACCUGGGCGGGGGCUGCUGCGGCUUUCUUUAGGUUGGGCCUUUUACUGAGGAGAUUUAAAUUCCCUCAAGUGUAAGGUAGCACCCCUACCUAUUAUCACCCAGAAUGGGUCCCUGCGGUGUUGGGAAAAUUCUCCCUGGGGGUAAGGUACCAGCCCUGUCCUUUAUGGGCUUCUUGUUCUAAAGCAUAUCCGUCCCAUAUGGUUGCUGCUAGUCACAUGUGGUGAUUAGUAACUAGUUAAAAAUGAAAAAUUCAGUUCCUCCAUUACACUUGCCACAUUUCAGAUGUUCAGUGGCCAACAGAUAUGCGCAAAUAGAGUGUUUCCAGCAUUGCAAAGUUCUGUUGGAUAGCACUGUUUGCCAGAUGUUCCCUUCUUUGUGGGUGAGGACUCUUUUGGUGUGACUUCCCUCUGUAUUGAGGCUCUUGUUCCUCAGUAUGGGGCUGUUUCUGUCUUUACAGUAAGUGACUACUCCAGGGUUCCCUGCCCUGCACACGUAGAGUGGGAGCGGCCCGUGGAUCCCAGGGAACUGUGCUUUUCAUUGUAGGCCCCCUCCCUGGAGGGGAAGAGGGCAAUCUCCGCUGGUAUCUCAGAAGUCUUCUUCUGAGGCAUAAGCCUCUCUUCCCAGGGCUCCCCUGGUCUCGCUGUCAGGCCCUAAGGUAUGUCUUCCCUUGGACUAAAGCUCCUUGGAACUCCCUUUUGACCUCAGUCUUCUCUGGGUUCCAGGUAACUUCCUUUAAAAUAAAGACGCUCCUCUCUUGAAGUUUUGGGUUCCUGCCCUGAUGGUCUAUGUCUCCCUGACUCUAAAUUACCAAUCCACUUGCUAUGGGAUUCCUCCAUGAGUGCAGAUCGGCUCCCUCACAGCUGCGGUACCUUUGCACCCUCUUAUCUUAGUAAGAUUUCUGUCUUCUCCCAGGUCUCUCUUGGGUACUGCCUUCUGCCCCCAAAUCUCUAAGCCUUCUUGGUAUUAGCUUCUUUGGGUUAGGAGUGUUAUUUCCUUUUGGUUUAAGGAUCCUGCUCUGGAAUAAAUGUCUUGGUGGUUUGAGUCCCUUCUACUUGGCAUUCAGCCCUGUCUGCAUGAGCGGGUUCAGCUCUUCACAGCUUUCGGCAUCUCUGCUCGCCGUCGUUUUCCCCCACCCCCAAUCUUUCUUCUCCUACCUACAGCUUACACACACACACACACACACACACACACACACACACACGCCCUUCUCUGUGAGCUGCCAGUUUCAUUUGUCUCCUGACUUGUCUGAGGGAUGACCUCUCCUAGCCACCUCUGCCCAGCCCCUCUGAGUAGGAAGUGUGAUUUCCAGGGCUAAUGCCUCCAUCCCAGUCAUCAGCUGUGUGCAGCAUGACUGUCCUGCUCUGAAAAACCUUUUUGAGUGUAUUCUGGGGAGAAGGUACUCCAUGCUCUAGGAAUUUUCCACUUCCUGAGUCAGAGGCACACAAAAAACAGCGUCCGUCUCCAAGAGAGUAUGAAGAGAGUGCGUCUGUAGGGCAGGGAAGAUGGCGGACAAGCGCAAACUCCAAGGUGAGAUUGAUCGCUGCCUCAAGAAGGUGUCCGAGGGCGUGGAGCAGUUUGAAGAUAUUUGGCAGAAGCUCCACAAUGCAGCCAACGCGAACCAGAAAGAAAAGUAUGAGGCUGACCUAAAGAAGGAGAUUAAGAAGCUACAACGGCUGAGGGACCAAAUCAAGACAUGGGUAGCGUCCAACGAGAUCAAGGACAAGAGGCAGCUUAUAGACAACCGCAAGCUCAUUGAGACGCAAAUGGAACGGUUCAAAGUUGUGGAACGAGAGACCAAAACCAAAGCUUACAGCAAAGAGGGCCUGGGCCUGGCCCAGAAGGUAGAUCCUGCCCAGAAGGAGAAGGAAGAGGUUGGCCAGUGGCUCACGAAUACCAUCGACACGCUCAACAUGCAGGUGGACCAGUUUGAGAGUGAAGUGGAGUCACUGUCAGUGCAGACACGCAAGAAGAAGGGCGACAAGGAUAAGCAGGACCGGAUUGAGGGCUUGAAGCGGCACAUCGAGAAGCACCGCUACCACGUGCGCAUGCUAGAGACCAUCCUGCGCAUGCUGGACAAUGACUCCAUCCUCGUUGACGCCAUCCGCAAGAUCAAGGACGACGUUGAGUACUAUGUUGACUCAUCCCAGGACCCCGACUUCGAGGAGAACGAGUUUCUCUACGAUGACCUGGACCUCGAGGACAUUCCACAGGCGCUGGUCGCCACCUCCCCUCCCAGCCACAGCCACAUGGAGGAUGAGAUCUUCAACCAGUCCAGCAGCACGCCCACCUCAACCACCUCCAGCUCUCCCAUCCCGCCCAGCCCAGCCAACUGUACCACGGAAAACUCUGAAGAUGAUAAGAAGAGGGGACGUUCCACAGACAGUGAAGUCAGCCAGUCUCCAGCCAAAAACGGCUCCAAGCCUGUCCACAGCAACCAGCACCCUCAGUCCCCAGCUGUGCCGCCCACCUACCCCUCCGGCCCCCCGCCUGCUGCCUCUGCCUUGAGCACCACUCCUGGCAACAAUGGGGUCCCCGCCCCCGCAGCACCCCCAAGUGCCCUGGGCCCCAAGGCCAGUCCAGCUCCCAGCCACAACUCGGGCACCCCUGCUCCCUAUGCCCAGGCUGUGGCCCCACCAGCUCCCAGUGGGCCCAGCACGACCCAGCCCCGGCCCCCCAGCGUCCAGCCUAGCGGAGGCGGAGGCGGCGGCAGCGGAGGUGGAGGGAGCAGCAGCAGUAGUAACAGCAGUGCCGGUGGAGGGGCUGGCAAGCAGAAUGGCGCCACCAGUUACAGCUCAGUUGUGGCAGACAGCCCGGCAGAGGUGGCUUUGAGCAGCAGUGGGGGCAACAAUGCCAGCAGCCAGGCCUUGGGCCCCCCUUCCGGCCCCCACAACCCACCUCCCAGCACCUCGAAGGAACCCAGUGCGGCAGCCCCAACGGGGGCUGGGGGCGUGGCCCCAGGCUCAGGGAACAACUCAGGGGGACCCAGCCUCCUGGUGCCACUGCCUGUGAAUCCUCCCAGCUCCCCAACGCCCAGCUUCAGUGAUGCCAAGGCAGCCGGUGCCCUGCUCAAUGGGCCUCCACAGUUCAGCACCGCCCCAGAAAUCAAGGCCCCUGAGCCUCUGAGCUCCUUGAAGUCCAUGGCGGAACGGGCAGCCAUCAGCUCUGGCAUUGAGGACCCUGUGCCAACGCUGCACCUGACCGAGCGAGACAUCAUCCUGAGCAGUACAUCAGCACCUCCGGCCUCAGCCCAGCCGCCCCUGCAGCUGUCAGAGGUGAACAUACCGCUGUCGCUGGGUGUCUGUCCACUGGGCCCUGUGCCCCUCACCAAGGAGCAGCUCUAUCAGCAGGCCAUGGAAGAGGCCGCCUGGCACCACAUGCCUCACCCCUCUGACUCUGAGCGUAUUCGGCAGUACCUCCCCCGGAACCCCUGUCCGACGCCCCCCUACCACCACCAGAUGCCACCCCCACACUCGGACACUGUGGAAUUCUACCAGCGCCUGUCGACCGAGACACUCUUCUUCAUCUUCUACUAUCUGGAGGGCACUAAGGCACAGUAUCUGGCAGCCAAGGCCCUAAAGAAGCAGUCAUGGCGAUUCCACACCAAGUACAUGAUGUGGUUCCAGAGGCACGAGGAGCCCAAGACCAUCACUGACGAGUUUGAGCAGAUCCCAGACCACCUCCUCGUCCACUCACUGACCGCCUUCUCCCCCGGCCAGGGCACCUACAUCUACUUUGACUACGAGAAGUGGGGCCAGCGGAAGAAGGAAGGCUUCACCUUUGAGUACCGCUACCUGGAGGACCGGGACCUCCAGUGACACCGGCCCCUCCCUCUACCCACCCCCUUCCCCCGCAUGCUGAUCCCCCUGCCCAGGUGAGGGCCCUGCCCUGGAAGACUGGAGGGAGGCCCCAAGCCACGGGGCAUCCCCCUCUCCCAGGAAGCAGGGAGGGGGCCGGGAGGUUUUCCUCUCAGCCCCACCCUGGGGGCCCGGGGGCGAGGGCUGCCCCCUCCUCCCCUCCCCAGUGAGGGACAUUUUUUGGUAAACCUAUUUUCAUUUUGGAAAAUAUUUAUGAAUAAAUAGUUUUAUAUGA